GUCAUUGCUUUGGGCUGGGGCCAUGGGAAGAAACCAUUGUGUGGCAGGGAAGGAGGUGGCUCUUGGCCCAGGCCUAAACCAGGAAAGCCUGGGAAACUGGGACCCACAGGUGGGCAUGAAAGGGCCGCAGCAGGGGCUCCCAGCAGUGUGUAAGACCGGGAGCUGGUCUGGCACCACUGCCCUGGUCCUUCCAGCUGCCUGUCACUGGUAUGAUGGCCCCGGUGCAUUGUGCCACCAGCAGGCCACAGCUGUGGAUCUUGGAAGGCCUCUGGGGUCCCCCGGGAGCAGGGGAGUGGGUGUGGGGGGGAACGGAUGGUGGUGAGAGGGACAGACCAGGCAGGCCCUGCCCCCGGGGCCCAUGCAGACCCUCAUCUUUUUCGACAUGGAGGCCACUGGCUUGCCCUUCUCCCAGCCCAAGGUCACGGAGCUGUGCCUGCUGGCUGUCCACAGAUGUGCCCUGGAGAGCCCCCCCACCUCUCAGGGGCCACCUCCCACAGUUCCUCCACCACCGCGUGUGGUAGACAAGCUCUCCCUGUGUGUGGCUCCGGGGAAGGCCUGCAGCCCUGCAGCCAGCGAGAUCACAGGUCUGAGCACAGCUGUGCUGGCAGCGCAUGGGCGUCAAUGUUUUGAUGACAACCUGGCCAACCUGCUCCUAGCCUUCCUGCGGCGCCAGCCACAGCCCUGGUGCCUGGUGGCACACAAUGGUGACCGCUACGACUUCCCCCUGCUCCAAGCAGAGCUGGCUAUGCUGGGCCUCACCAGUGCUCUGGAUGGUGCCUUCUGUGUGGAUAGCAUCACUGCGCUGAAGGCCCUGGAGCGAGCAAGCAGCCCCUCAGAACACGGCCCAAGGAAGAGCUAUAGCCUAGGCAGCAUCUACACUCGCCUGUAUGGGCAGUCCCCUCCAGACUCGCACACGGCUGAGGGUGAUGUCCUGGCCCUGCUCAGCAUCUGUCAGUGGAGACCACAGGCCCUGCUGCGGUGGGUGGAUGCUCACGCCAGGCCUUUCGGCACCAUCAGGCCCAUGUAUGGGGUCACAGCCUCUGCUAGGACCAAGCCAAGACCAUCUGCUGUCACAACCACUGCACACCUGGCCACAACCAGGAACACUAGUCCCAGCCUUGGAGAGAGCAGGGGUACCAAGGAUCUUCCUCCAGUGAAGGACCCUGGAGCCCUAUCCAGGGAGGGGCUGCUGGCCCCACUGGGUCUGCUGGCCAUCCUGACCUUGGCAGUAGCCACACUGUAUGGACUAUCCCUGGCCACACCUGGGGAGUAGGCCAAGAAGGAAAAUCUGACGAAUAAAGACCCCCGCUGCCCCAUA